AGUUCCCUUCCUGCGGCGUCCUCCACACCCGGGGUCUGCUGGUCUCCGCGGAUGUCACAGGCUCGGCAACCGCCCUCCUGUCGGCGGGGAGUCCCGCGACGCCCGGAAAUGCUCCGAAGCCUGUCGCCCAGCUGCCAGAUCUGCGUCUGUGUCCGGUUCCGUCACUGAGGUCGCCCCUGUCCGGCCCUUCCACCCUAGUUCUCUUCACCGUCCGCCCAUCCUAUCGCGCGCGGCCUCAGGUCCCGAUUCGGCAUGUGGCUUGUCUUCCAUCGUCCCCACCCUCGCCCCUCUUGGCCCCUCAGGGCAGCCCUGGGAUUCGGCAGACGCCAGUCCUCCCUGAGAUGCUUCCCCAUCCUUCCCUCCGCCAGGCCCUACGUCUCCGCAAACCCCACGCUUCGGGGUGGCCGCCUCAGACAGGACCCUGAGUCCGAGACUGGGGUAGGGGACCUGCCCGAUCCUGUAACAACCCUCGUGCUUCUGCACAAUCGCCUCCCACUAGCGGUGACUGUUGGGUGUUUACCUUCCCGGUGUCCCACUGAGAAGCGGGCUCUUCCUUGGCAGGGGCUUCUUCAUUGCCUCGCUGUGGAUGUCGAGGUGGGGCAGGAGAGUGAGGAGAAAACAGAGGAGGGAGGUAGAGCCAACGAGCGAGAAAAGGGGAGGGAAGUUUAGAUGGGAAGUGGAUGGGUCUGAGGAAUUUGAACAAACACCGACAAUGAAGGAGAGUGACCUGAGCAAGUAGUAGUGGGGUAAAUGGAAAUAGACAAAAUGGGAAUCAGCAGAGAUAUGGAGGACAGAAUACAAUGAGGAGGCCUUGACCGUCAGUAGCAGAGAGGGCAGCAGAAGCCUAAUUCCCAAAUUCUUUAGAUGGUUUUCUGAUUUCCAAAUUAGUUUCCCUUUUAAAUUUAUUGUGUCAGGUUCAGCUUAUGAGGCCUCAAUACUUUUCAGUCUUAAUUGUAUAUUGAAAAUACUUUUUGUUUACUAAAUGCUUUUUACAUUAAUUCAGUGUGCACUUCGUAAGGAUAAUGAUGAUUUGAGUUAGUUUAGUAUUCAACAGCUUCCUCUAUUCCUUUAUAUGAUCUCUGUAUUUAAUGGCUGUGGCAUAAAGUUUCCAACUAAGUUUAAGUAUCAAGUUUUCUUUGUGCUGUUUUCUGCAAAUAUUGAAGGAUGACCUGGAUUGUCCUAGAACUUUGUUCCAACAGAUUACAUGUGUUCAUAAUGAAUAGACUGCUCAAAGAUAUUUCCAAAGCUCACCUUUUAUGUUUUUCAGUUCCAAUAAUUACAUCUUUUUAAGGUUUAUAUUUUUUGAUGACUUAAUGUGAUGUUCUGGAGAAGACAAAUGCUUUUAAUCAAUAUGAUUAAAACCGUGAAAGACAAAUCGCUGUUACUUAAGAGUGUGACAUAUGAUCUGAAAUCUUUAGGGGGCAGGGAUGUUAAGGGAAAACUGCCACUAUCGUAUUAAGGUCAUGCCAUUCCUGUGAAGCUGGUGCUUGUUACUCUCUACUGGCUUCUGUUCACCUUUCCACCGGCCCCAAGACACACACAUAGUGACACAAGGCAGUGGACAGGGAAAGAGCAAGACUUUAUAAAGUAAGCACACAACAAAGGUAUCUUUCUAAUGAGGAGGAGGUGUUGGUUCUGGGAAGGAAGCUUGGGAUUUGGGUAUUCAGGAUCCAGAAGUGAGAGAGCCUGGGAAGUUCAGGAACCAGAGAAAGAAAAAGCCUUGCCCAUUCUCACCCAUGACACUGUGCUCAGCAGGUACUAGCAGACUUCAGGCUCUGUGACUAAAAGGGGUCAGACCAGUUGAUAUACCCACAGCUGCCAUGUAAGGAUGUGUGUGGACUUCACUAGGGAAGAACGGUGUUAUGAAAGAAGGGGCAGAAAAACUCACCUGUUGGUCUGCAUGUAGAGGUUUAUUGUCCUGAAUUCCUGGAGGUUCAGUGAAAAGCAGAAGAUUGUCUUUUACACAUGUUGAGUUAUGCCCCCAUAUAUGUGGUUGUGGUAAAGAAAGAGGGUGUGUUGAUGAGAGGUCCUGAAAUGCAUUUUCCUAAUACUCAGCAGGGGCUUCUCAAGAAGGAUCUUCCCUAAGAAAGAAGCUCAGAGAACAAAAAUGGAAAAGGAUUAGAUAUGGCACUUUCACUGGAAAAAGUCAUGUUAUUCAUUGAUUGUUUUGUCAUCUCCCGCCUUAAGUGUUGUUUUUAGGAUGUGGUAAUCUCUGACCCUGCCUAACACAUUUCCCAACUCACCCAUAGCCUUCCCUUAACGUCCUCCCAUCUUCACGCUAUCACACUGUGACCCAGUGAAUUCGAACUUGUGAAGUUCCAUUCGGGGGAUCAUAUGGGAAGGGCUUCACACCCAGACAUAGAUUAUAGAUGGGAAGUGGGCCACAUGGUGUCAGUGAGGCAAGUAUGGGUCGUUUAGGGACAAUGCACUGUCAGAUCUUUGUUGACCAUGAUUAGAGAAACUGUGCAUAUUAGUAGUGAAUUAAUGUCAGGAAUAUCUGACAAAUCCUGGAAAAGAAGAUUGAUGAGAGGAAAUGUGUUCUGCCCAACUGUAUAAUGCAUUUGAAGCUUAAAACAAUGAAUCAGUAUUGAUCUGGCCACAAAAUAUUAAUGAUUUGAAUUAAAAAGAAAAGUUUAGAAAAUGAUAGCUUUGACAAAUUAAGGUAGCAUUUCAUCCACACGAUGGAGUGUGUUUUAUUCAGUAAUUGAUUUAAAAAUGGAAUCAACCUAAGUGUCUAACAGGAGGGAGUUUUAUAAAUUGUUCACAGAACAUCUGUUCCAAGGAGACCUUGAUGUUCAUAGAUUUGUAAAGAAUGCUGCUUACUAGCACACUGACUGCUCUGCAAAUGUCUGAGGGUUCCUCCACUUGGGGCAAGUUGGGGGUUUGAUCGCAGAGUAAAUAAAUGGUGCAUUUUAUAAUGUAAUAUAUUCUAGCAAGAUGCAGCCCACAAACUGUAUAGAUACUCUUAUGUACCACAUAAAGUUCAUCUACUACUUUAACCAGAACUUGAUACUGUAUGUAUGUUUUUUUUUUUUAGAUUUGGAUAAAAUGACAACUCAUUGUUAUUUCCAGUUCACAAAGUAAUUGUGAGGCUGAAUAAAUUUUAUUAUUUUAUAGACAUAUGUGUAAAAUGAAUUUUUCUAUGAAACUCAUUUUUGAUGUAUAUUAGAUGCUAUUUUAUAUUCUGUAGUUUAAUUAUAUGUACGCACACACAAACACACACUUCGGUGUCUUAUUAUGUUUCUGCAGUGAAACCAAAAUCCUUCCUUCACGCCCUUUGAUUUUAUGUUUUCCUCAGGAAGGCAGGAGCUAUUGUAUAUGAUAAAAUAUUAUGUUUUAUUCAGUCCACUUAUGAAAUUGUUUAAUAUUGUUAUAAAUAUUUAUAUGACUUAUUUUAAAUUUCCAAAUAACAUAGGUUACAUGAAAUUUGACAACUUUAUUUUUUUCUUUUCACAACUAUUUUGACUGUAUACUCACCAAAAAUCAAAAUUUAGACAAAAUUGACUUUUAGACUAAUUCUCAUUUUUUACAUGUAAAAGACCACAUGGGACUUUUAAGUCUAGGUUGCCCUGAGUCUACAGUCACUGAGGUUUUAUGUCACUAUGUCCUCCAUUCUAAUAAUAGGAUUUUCAGGCUUUAUUCAUGUCAUUUUUAUAUCCUCAUUAAGUUUUAAAAUUUAUUUACAUGGGUCUACAAAUUUAUUUCAAAUCGUAGUCAUAAUAUUUGCCUGUUGUAAAUAGACACUGAUUUUGUGUGUUUGCUUUUUUUAAGGACUAAUGUUGCUAAACAGGAAAUAUUGAUUUCAGAAUAUUCAUAAUAGUUUUGCCCACUUUUUAAAUAUUCUUAUUAGUAUUGAUAAUUAGAAUUGAUUCCACUUUUUCAAGUUUACAGUCACGUCAUCUGAGAAUAACUACAGUUGCAGCUCUUUGACUCCAUUUUUGUAGUCCCUCUCCUUUUCCCUCUUGUUUUGGUCCCACCUCAGGCAUCAUGUGCAGUGGUGAAUGGCAUCAGCCUCACCCAGCCUCCUUUUUCCAGCCUUACCUUUAGUGGAAAUGGUUCUUUUGUUAACUGCUGAAUAUAUUGUUGAGAUUUUAUUGAUUAAGAAGAAUUAGUCCCCACAAUUUGGUAUGAUUUUUAAAGAUUUUAUAUUAUUUUUAAAGAUUUAAAUUAUAUGAAAAUGUUUUUUCAAAGGUCUAUUAAUGUGAUUUUUUUAAUCUUUAAAAUUACUUUGUGAAAAUGAUAGGUUUUCUAGUAUGGAAUUAUCCUUUUAUUAUUGCAAUAAACUCCACUUUACCAUGCUCUGUCAUUAUUUAACCAUACCAGUGAUGGCCAGGUGGCCAAAAUAAAUAGCCAAAUGGCUAAAAUUGUAUUGAUGAUUUUUGCAAAUGUAAGUAAGGAAAAUUGUUGGUUAAAUUUGUAGUUAUUGUUACAUUCAUGUUCAUUUUGAUUAGCAUAAUAAACUAAUGAGGACAGGCUUAUUUUUCUCCUUCAAAAUAACUUAGGUUACAAAGGAACUAGAAGUGAUUUCACAUGUAAGAACUCUCACAAAUCACUUUUACAGUUAAACUCUGAUAUAUAACUUAAACAUUAAAAUUGGCUAAUCAGAUUUUUGUGCUGAUUAAUGAGGGAAAGUUUUUACUCUUUUUGUGGAAAGUAAUAUACAUAUUCAUGUUGGAAUAUAAUUAUUCCCAUUUCUUAGAUUUUAAAUUACUACUUUUAAAUAAAUACAGUCUCUUUUAUUAACCUGUGUUUUUUCUUUCCACCGUGGGUCUUUUCAGUUUCAUGAUUUUGCUCUCAAAACUUUUUAAUUAUUGAUUUCUGUCAAAUCUGUUCAUUCAUUACAUUAUUUUAUUAUUUAUUAAAUUGUUUUAUCUUUUUAAGUCUUAUUAAUAUGUACUGAAUUUGUAACAAUUUGGAAAGUCAAGUAACUCCUGUUUUAUCUUUUUCUUGGUUUAUGAGUGUUUUUAAAGUUUUACGUUUCUUGAAGAUCACAGCUGUAGCCCCAAUUCCAUGGUUCUGGCUACUUACAUUUAUCAUACUUAUUAAUAUCAUGAAUGUAAUUGGAAUACCCCUUUGAUUUUACUGGUGACGUAUACCCACUAGUGUACUGAGACGGAAAAAAAAGUCUUUAGAACUCAGAUAAAUAUACAGUUCAUAUUUACUAUUUAUGUAUGUGUGAUCUCAUUAUUAAAUUACUCUAUCAUGUUUGUGGAAUUAGCAGUUUCUCUUUGAAUUUGGAUGUUUCUAGUUAUGUGUAUUUCCAACGUAUGUUUUUAGCCACAUACACUUUAUUGAAUAUCAUAUUUGGUGUUUAAUUUUUGCUAGGAUUAUAGGCUGGACUCCAGAUCCAAACUUGACAUGUAGCAGACCCAUUAAAAACAUACAUUAAGCCCCUAGCACUGUUUUAAUCUCCAUGGCCUGGCUGAGCUUCUGCCAUCUGUCUUCCUAGGCACCAUGAGGUCUGGACAUCUCAUUUGGCAUAACUCAGCUGUGGCCAUUGGUGGAUCUCAUCCUUAGUACUAGUCCCUGCUGGCAGGGGUGACCCAGGCCCACAUAAGCCAUUGCUGGCCUCCUUGGAGGACUUAGAGAAUCCUGAGAUUGCCCAUGAGGAUGGACAUGCCUUUCAGUCUAGCACCCACCUUUAGUGAUGCCUGUGGAGAUUGAGAAGCUCACAGGGGCCUUGGAUGUCUUUCUUAUACCUCCAUUGUCUGCAGCGUGACUCCCAUACUCUUGAGCCAAGGUAGAGAAUUUUUAGGAGGCUUGUGUGGAGGUUUAUGGUGGCCCCCAUGGUUCUGUGAGACUGGUAGAAAGCACAGACCCCUUAGACUUCUCCCCAAGGAGAAUACGUGAGACUAGUGGAGGAAAGGAGAGUAAUGAAAUAUGCAUUUCGUGUCCCAGGCUAUCAGAGCACAGCUCUAAGGAAAAAUACAGGGCAUCGUAUAGCAACUGGCACAGCUCUGUGAGACUGGGAGAUAUUGCACAACCUUGAAAAAUCAAGAUGUGACCCUACUGAAUGAACAAAAUAAAUCUCCAAUAAUUGACCAUAAAGAAAUACAGGUUUCUGGCUGGGUGCGGUGGCUCACACUUGUAAUCACAGCACUUUGAGAGGCCGAGGUAGGCAGAUCAUUUGAGGCCAGGAGUUCAAAAUCAGCUUUGCCAACAUGGUGAAAUACAAAAAAAAAAAAAAAAAAAAAAAAAAAAAUUAGCUGGUCGUGGUGACGGGCACCUAUAAUCCCAGCUACUCAGGAGGCUGAGGCAGGAGAAUCACUUGAAUCCAGGAGGUGGAGGUUGCAGUGAGCUGGUAUCGUGCCGUUGCACUACAGCCUGGGCAACGCGAGUGAAACUCCGCUUUAAAAAAAAGAAAAAGAAAUGGAGGUUUCUGAUUUUCCUGAUAAGAAUUACAGGUAAUUGCCUUAAAGGAGGUCAAUGAGCUAUGAGACAACACUGAUAACAAGUAAAAUCUGGAAAAGGAUACAUGAACAACAUGAGAAUAUCAACAAAGAAAAACCAUAAUAAAAGAAUCAAAUAUAGAUUCUGGGGCUGAAGAAUACAGUAACUGAACUGGAUCAAUACAAGGCUUCAAGAGCUGACUUGAUCAAGCAGAAGAAAGAACCAGUGAACUCAAAGACAGGUUAUUUGAAAUUAUUCAAUCAGAAGAGCAAGUAGAAAAAGAAUUUUUUAAAAGUGAAGAAACUGUCUGUCUUUGCUAAAAAUUGGAGGGUCCUAAGAACUCCUCCCCGCCCCCACUGCCAAUGCAGAGUCUUACUCUGUCACCCAGGCUGGAGUGCAGUGGUUCGAUCUCCGCUCACUGCAACCUCCACCUCCCAGGUUCAAGCGAUUCUCAUACCUCAGCCUCCCGAAUAGCUGAGAUUACAGGUGCCUGCCACCAUGCCCAGCUAAUUUUUGUAUUUUUAGUAGAAACGGGGUUUUGGGGUUUCACCAAGUUGGCCAGGCUGGUUUUGAACUUCUGACCUCAGGUGAUCCUCCUGCCUUGGCCUCCCAAAGUGCUGGGAUUACAGGCGUGAGCCACCAUGCCCGGCAAGAACUCCUUUUUAUGUUAGAUUCACUAGGGUUUAGCAGCUCACAGAACCCAGGAAAACAGUUUACUUAGCUGAUUUAUUACAAAGGACAUUUUAAAUAUUACAUAUGAACAGCCAGCUAAAGAGUUACAUACAGCAAGUUUUGGAAGCAUCUUAGGUUUAGGAGGUCUGUCUCCAAGCAGUUGGGGGGUACCAUUGUUUCAGCAUAUGGAUGUGUUCUUCACCCACCCAGAAGCUCUAGGAAUCCCAUCAUUCAGGGAUUUUUAUGUGGUGUUCAUCAAGUAGGCAUAAUUGUUAUUAACUCGAUCUCCAGCCUCUGUCCCUUUCCCAAAGGAUAGGGGGUGGGACUGUACGUUCCAAGCUUCUGAUCAAGUCAUGGUCUUUCAGGUGAUCACCCCCCAUCCUAGAGCCUAGUAAUAAUUGUCUCAUUAGAACAGAAGACACUCUUAUCACCUAUGAAGUUCCAAGGCAUUACGAGCUCUGUACUGGGAACCAGGGUCAAAGACCAAAAAGAACAAAAGCUUCUCCUAGCAACUCUGUUGCUUAGGAAAUUACAAGGGUUUUGGGUGGCUCUGUGCCAGGAACUGGGGAUGAAAACCAAACUAUCUAUUUCUUACAACUAACAAUGUCACAUACAUGUUCAAGUUUUCAUGUUCUUAGUGUCCUUUCAUUUCAACUUGAGGAACUCCCUUUAGCAUUUCUUGUAAGGUAUGUCACUUGUAAAGUGUGUCUUUUAAGGAAUCCACCAUGAUAAAAUGAAAUUUGAAGCUGCUUGGUAGAUAAAUUCAUGCUACAUUUAUCUACAGGUCAGACUUGAGGGACUGGUAUUUCUAGAAGCCUCACAUGGAAGAGACAGAAUCAUUCAGUACAAGUGUAUCCAGAGGACCAGCAGAAGGGAGAAGGAAUGGAGGGAGGCUCCUGAGGGCUGAGAUGCAUGUGGAGAAAGCCUGCAAGCACACAAACCGAGAAUAAUUAAAUCUGAGAAAUUCCAGGAUUUAUCUAUUUGUCUUCUUAGUGCUUGGAUGGUGUGAGUGAAAACCCAGAGGAAUACAUUUGGUGGCUGAGCUAGUACAAUGCCAUCACCGGAUUCCAUGACCUUCGAGGAUAUCAUUGUAGACUUCACUCAAGAAGAGUGGGCCCUGCUGGACACAUCCCAGAGAAAGCUGUUUCAAGAUGUGAUGUUGGAGAACAUCAGUCAUCUGGUCUCUAUUGGCAAACAGCUCUGCAAAUCAGUUGUGCUUUCCCAAUUGGAGCAAGUAGAGAAACUUUCAACACAAAGAAUAAGCUUACUGCAAGGUAGAGAAGUUGGCAUUAAACAUCAAGAGAUACCAUUCAUUCAACAUAUCUAUCAGAAGGGCACGUCCACCAUCAGCACAAUGAGAUCUCAUACUCAAGAGGAUCCUUUUCUAUGCAAUGACUUAGGAGAAGAUUUCACUCAACAUAUAGCAUUGACUCAAAAUGUGAUUACCUACAUGAGAACGAAACACUUUGUAAGCAAAAAGUUUGGGAAAAUCUUCAGUGACUGGUUAUCCUUUAAUCAACACAAGGAAAUUCACACCAAAUGUAAAUCAUAUGGAAGUCAUCUAUUUGAUUAUGCCUUUAUCCAAAACUCUGCCCUUAGACCACACAGUGUGACUCACACUAGAGAGAUAACAUUGGAAUGUCGUGUGUGUGGGAAAACCUUUAGCAAAAAUUCUAAUCUUAGGCGACAUGAGAUGAUUCACACUGGAGAGAAACCACACGGAUGUCAUCUAUGUGGGAAAGCCUUUACUCAUUGCUCUGAUCUUCGAAAACAUGAGAGAACUCACACUGGAGAGAAGCCAUAUGGAUGUCAUCUAUGUGGGAAAGCCUUCAGUAAAAGUUCUAACCUUAGACGACAUGAGAUGAUUCACACUAGAGAAAAAGCACAGAUAUGCCAUCUAUGUGGGAAAGCCUUCACUCAUUGCUCUGACCUUAGAAAACAUGAGAGAACUCACUUAGGAGAUAAACCAUAUGGAUGUCUCCUAUGUGGGAAGGCUUUCAGUAAAUGUUCUUACCUUAGACAACAUGAAAGAACUCACAAUGGAGAGAAACCAUAUGAAUGUCAUCUAUGUGGAAAAGCCUUCUCUCAUUGUUCUCACCUUAGACAACAUGAGCGAAGUCACAAUGGAGAGAAACCACAUGGAUGUCAUCUAUGUGGGAAAGCAUUCACUGAAUCUUCUGUGCUUAAACGACAUGAGAGAAUUCACACUGGAGAGAAACCAUAUGAGUGCCAUGUAUGUGGGAAAGCCUUCACUGAAUCUUCUGACCUCAGACGACAUGAGAGAACUCACACUGGAGAAAAACCAUAUGAAUGCCAUCUAUGCGGAAAAGCCUUCAAUCACUCUUCUGUCCUUAGACGACAUGAGAGAACUCACACUGGAGAGAAACCAUAUGAAUGCAAUAUAUGUGGUAAAGCCUUCAAUAGAAGUUACAACUUUAGACUUCAUAGAAGAGUUCACACUGGAGAGAAACCAUAUGUAUGUCCUCUAUGUGGGAAAGCCUUUAGUAAAUUUUUUAACCUUAGACAACAUGAGAGAACUCACACUAAAAAAGCAAUGAAUAUGUAAGAAUCAUCAGCUGUAGCGUUAACACUAAAUACACCAAGGACAAACAUACUACAGGAAUAUUAUGUCUGUAAUCAGUGUGGAAAAGCCUUUAUUUAUAUUUACCACUUUGCUCAACCUAAAUGAAUUCAAGGUAGAGAGAAUCCAGAUGUAUUUAAUGUUUAUGGCACAAACUUCAGACUCUAGGCUGACCAUAUACAACGUGAGAGAAUGAAACUAUAGAUCAAAGGAAUGUGGAGGAGUCUUCAUCCACAGCUCUGUUAAAUAAAUGGGAGAAAUCACAUCACGAAAAUUCUGUGCCUGUCGUCAGUGUGAAAAUGCCUUUGCUGAUAAUUUAUCCUCUAAACAAAUGAGUAAAAUCCACAGGCAAGCAACCAUAUGUCUGUAAUUGCUGUGCACUCUCAUUCAGCUAAGCACCAAUUUUGGUGUGUGCAAGAAAAUUCAUUAUAAGGUAACUGAUAAAAACAGGAAAUAUGUGAAAAUAUUUUUUAUUAGGUGGAUGAGGCCUCUUGAACAAUUCCAGACAUUCAUAGUGGAGAAGUUAUUCAAUGAAAACUCAUGAGAAAUCCUUUUCUUAAUACAGCAGCACUUCUAUAAUAGAUCAGAAUUCACAUGGUGUAGAACUCUCAAUGACAUGAAUGGAGGGUAGUCCUCAGUAAAUUACUCAUUCCUUAGUCAAUACCAGCAUUUUUCCAGUGAGAAAACUAUCUUGACAGGAUAGUGGAAAAACCUUCAGGCAGCUUUUAUGUCAAAAAAGUGAGACAGGGAUGAAAACUCUAAAAAGCCAUUGAUGAGAUGUAUAGCUGGGGGACAAAACAUAAAGCCAUCAAGCACGUGCUUGAGAAAAAAAUUAUAAUUUUGAAUAAAGACUUUCUACUUAAAAUAUGUGGGUUGAAAUGUACAAUUCUGAAAUAACCUGGGAAUAUUGAAUGCAGAAUUAUGUAAGAAGUAAUAAGAUUAAAUUAGUACUGUCAAAAAUAC